GGGAGCGGCACGGCAGCCACUGCUUGGGGUAGCGGGAGGGCAGACUCUGGGCGCCACUCCCGGGCCGGUCAUGAACGGGCCGGCGGACGGCGAAGUGGACUACAAAAAAAAAUACCGGAAUCUGAAGCGGAAGCUCAAGUUCCUCAUCUACGAGCACGAGUGCUUCCAGGAGGAGCUGAGGAAAGCGCAAAGGAAAUUACUGAAGGUGUCCCGGGACAAGAGUUUCCUCCUAGACCGACUUCUGCAGUACGAGAACGUGGAUGAAGACUCUUCGGACUCAGAUGCCACUGCAUCAUCAGAUAACAGCGAGACGGAGGGGACACCCAAGUUGUCUGACACACCGGCCCCUAAGAGGAAGAGAAGCCCUCCGCUGGGGGGCGCCCCCUCUCCCUCCAGCCUCUCCCUGCCUCCUUCAACAGGGUUUCCCCUUCAGGCCUCCGGGGUCCCCUCCCCAUACCUGAGCUCGCUGGCCUCCUCCCGCUACCCCCCAUUCCCUUCUGACUACCUGGCCCUGCAGCUGCCCGAGCCCAGUCCCCUGAGGCCCAAGCGGGAGAAACGGCCCCGCCUGCCCCGGAAACUCAAGGGGAGCGGGAGUCCCUGAAGGGCCAGGGGAGUGAGGAGAUGGAAGGAAGGGAGUCCAAGCAGAGGAAGGAUAGCUGUGAAGACAGAAGCAGGUUGGUUCUGUCAGGCCUGAGUUGGACUUGGCCAGCUUUGAAUCCCAGCUCUUCCAGUGCUCACCAUGCGACCUCAGCGUUGUCAUUUCACUCUUUAAGCCACAGCUCUCUUUCUCCAUUCAGUGGCGGCAUUGUGCGGAGAAUGUGAGUGAAGGGAUGAAAAUCGCUCGGCCCGUGCCUGGCCCCUAGUAAGCCACAGAGAAAUGUGAGCCGCUGCCAGUCAGGCUGAGAGGACGCCACUGAGGAAGUCCAGGCCAGGGUGGGACAUGCUGCGCACAGUGGGGAAGGAGAGGAGGUGGCCAGAGGAGGGGAUGGUCCUUUCCAGUCAUACACGCAUGUCUGCUUGUGUGUGUACAUGUGGGGGCCUGGUGCAGGGCGUGGGGGUGCUGUUCAGAGUUGGACCCCCCAUCAUCCAUCCUGCCAGCCUCCUAUACCCUGAGGCCUGACCCACCCUGGCCCCCACACCACCCCAGCAGCGGAGAUGAGGGUAAGUGAGGGCUCCUUAGGAAGCAGAGAGGAGGCCACAGGGCCAAAUGUGACACUCAGAAGGGCCACUGGAGACCACGCAUGGCGUUUCCUGCCAGCCCACUCAGCAUCUAGCCCAGGGCCAGACUGGACACUGCCCCGCAGGACCCAGCAGGCCUAAGCCUCAGGACCUCCAUGUCCACACCAGGUUCAGCCUCCUCUGCUGGCACGUGACUUCUCCCCGUUUCCCGCCCCCCAGUGUCCUGAGGCUGGGAGGGCAUUAACAGAAACCACCUGACACACAGCAGGUGCCCAGUUUGUGCCCACAGACAAAGCACGGGGACUGCAGAGGAGACCCACAGAGCUCUCUAGGGAGGGUUUGUGAGGACCUGGCAGCGGGGGGGAGCUGAAGGGUUGAGCAGGGCAGAGGCCACUUCCCACCCUCAGAGGACAAAGCAGGACUUCUGACAAAUAGAGCAGGAUGCCCAGGGGGAGGGGCUGCCUGUCGUCCCGCAGGCGGCACUCCCGCCCCGAGGCCCCGAGUGGCACGGUGACGCGCUCAGGUCUGUGUUUUAGAGCGCGCGCUCUGGCUGCCGUGCGGAGGAGCUGGAUCUGGGAGAGGCUGCGGGCAGGGAGUCCAGUUAGGAGGCUGGGACCGCAGCCCAGGUGAGCUAAGAGGAGGGCUGGGCCUAGGCCACAGCUGCCGGGACCCCGAGGAGGGGCCCAUCCAAGACAUAAUACAAGCUUCUUGGGGGCAGAUAAGCCGCUGGGGCUCCUGGCUCAGGCAGCCUGCAAUACCCUCCACCGAACCAGUGAGUGCCGCAGAAGAGGGAGAGGAGGAGUAGGGAGAGGAAGCUGGUGGCAGGUGGCACCUCCGGGGCCGGCAGGCAGGCAAGCACUCCAGGCCGACUCCGCCUCUGGCUUAACCCCUGUCUCAGGGCAGCCCAGGCGCCUCCCUGGAGAGGGCAGGUGCCCGGGCCUUUCCCUCCCGGUUUCCUGUGAGACACCCCCAUCCCCUCAUCUCACCUCUAUCACCACCCCCAGGCACUUGCUGGUUUGAGGCUCUCGAGGGGCUGAGGGGGGCAGGCCCUGAGUGCAGCAUGGGUUGGCCCAGCUGUGCCCAGGGCCUCUUCCCCCUCCCCAGAGCUGCCCUGGGGGGCAAAGCCUAGUCUCCUGAGGCCCCAGUGCCUCCCUGACUAGUCCCCCUGUGUUUCUUCCCCCUGCUGCAGAUGGCGGUGGGACCCCCCGACUGCCCUGUGGGAGGGCCGCUGACCUUCCCUGGCCGGGGUUCUGGGGCUGGGGUCGGGACAACCCUGACCCCCCUCCCACCCCCUAAGAUGCCCCCCCCCACGAUCCUGAGCACGGUCCCUCGGCAGAUGUUCAGCGAUGCAGGUAGCGGGGACGAUGCCUUGGAUGGAGACGAUGACCUGGUGAUCGACAUCCCGGAGUGACCGUGACAUCACGCCAUGCCCACCACGGCCCCGCCCGGCGCCCUCCCCGUGCCAGCACACACGAGUCCAGCUUCCUCGGAGGUGUUUAUUGAUGCCCAGCUGCCAUGCUCCGGCCACUGACACAACCAGAAAAGGCGUAAACAUGCACGGGUGUCCCCCAGGAGGGUGGCAGGGGCCCUGCCUUCAAACCCCGGCCCCCUCCAGGGGACAGUUAUUUAAACGAGUGGCCGGGAGCAUCUGCCACCUGCUGGGGAGGCAGAGACCCUGCAAUGGCCACCUCUUUAAAAGGGCAGCUGUACAGGGCUAGGUUUUUUCAAUGAAGUUUCUGUAUUAAAGGAGUGGCUCUGGG